GUGUUACGUCACAGUGGGCGGAAGUCGCGGCCGCUGUUUUGAAAUCGGGCCGCGGGGGGUCUCUCAAGCUGGUUCCAACGCUGAGGCCCCACAGCCUCCCAAUUCCGGGCAGACCCCUGACACCUGCUGUCUGGCCCCUUCCGGCCUGAAGCUGCAGCCGCGCCAUGUCCACCCCUCCGUUGGCCGCGUCGGGGAUGGCGCCCGGGCCCUUCGCCGGGCCCCAGGCUCAGCAGGCCGCCCGGGAAGUCAACACGGCGUCGCUGUGCCGCAUCGGGCAGGAGACAGUGCAGGACAUCGUGUACCGCACCAUGGAGAUCUUCCAGCUCCUGAGGAACAUGCAGCUGCCAAAUGGUGUCACUUACCACACUGGAACAUAUCAAGACCGGUUAACAAAGCUACAGGAUAAUCUUCGCCAACUUUCAGUUCUCUUCAGGAAGCUGAGAUUGGUAUAUGACAAAUGCAAUGAAAACUGUGGUGGGAUGGAUCCCAUUCCAGUCGAGCAACUUAUUCCAUAUGUGGAAGAAGAUGGCUCAAAGAAUGAUGAUCGGGCUGGCCCACCUCGUUUUGCUAGUGAAGAGAGGCGAGAAAUUGCUGAAGUAAAUAAAGCAUUGUCCUCAGUACCAGAAUUUCUUCCAUGAAGCAGCUGGAUGUGUUGUCGGCUAUAUACUCAUUUCACAUGAGUGGACAAGUUUCUUCUUGGAGAACAUAAGACUCCAGUGGAAACAAAGCAGCACCUGUUUCAUGUACCCAUUUCAUGUUUUGAUGAAUAUUUACAGAAACAAAAGUAUUGUGCCAUAUUUUUAAUACAUUGGCAUUUGGUUGUAUUAAAUAAGUUGCUUUAUAGAUCUGUGUAAUUUAUAAUAAAAUUAUAUUAUUUGCAUUCAAUUAAAAAGUCAGAAUUUUAUUACAAUGAAUAUUUUCUUUCUUUCUAAAUAAGCUACCUAAAAUAAGUAGAUUUAUAUACCCCUCAGCUGACCCUCAGUCAUUUUCAAGAUAUUAUCAUAUCAUUGUGUACUUGAAAUUGUGCAGAAGAACAUAUUGAUGGUGUGUUUACUAUUUAGUCGUUAUGGUCUGUCUGGUUUCUAACAAUACAAAAACCACCAAUAACUAUCCUGGUGCUAUGAAACUUUGAGGCACAUGAUUUGUAGUCAGUAUUUGAUGUAAAUCAUCAUAAGACAAUAUGGCUGGUUUUAAUAGUCAAAUUCGUGGUUUAUUUAAAUACUUUUCAUUUUCUCUUAAUAUAUCCUGGAAUCCUUAAGCCAAAUACCCAUUUAAAGGAUGGACACUUGUUUGAGACCAUAUGCUUUAGGUGCAGGGGUGUCCAAUCUUUUGGCUUCCCUGGGCCACAUUGUAAGAAGAAGAAUUGUUUUGGGCCACAUAUAAACUAUACUAACAUUAAUGAUAGCUGAGAAGCCAAAAUAUAAAAAAAUCACGAAAAACAUCUCAUAAUGUUUUAAGAAAGCUUACAAAUUUGUAUUGGGCUGCACUCACAGCCGACUGGGGCCACAUGUGGCCUGUGGGCCACAGUUGGACAAGCUUGCUUUGGGGACAUCAGAAUGAGUUUUAUUUUGCUUAACGCUCUUUUCUUGAUGGUAAAAUGAAAUUGAAAAAGAUAGUAGGUAGUAUUUACAAGGUUGGCAUUGAGUCCAUGCAUUUAGAAAGUAAACCAUUUUUUGUCAAGUGUCACAGCUUUUGUGUGAAUAUUACAUUACAUGGUAUCAGUUAGCAUCAACUUUUUUUAAGUAUUUAGUCUACUUACACAUUCGCCUGUUAAUGUACAAAAUUGGGCACAGCUGAUGGAUUUUGAAAAUAGCAGCUGUCAACGUCUGUUAAAAUCAAUCAGUGGCAAGACUGUGUAUAUUAAAUCCUAUAUCGUGUCAUGAAAAUUUAUUUACACUUUAGCCUCUAAUAAGCAUAAGUGUCAGCUUUGCUGUUGAUCAUUUUCAUGACAUGUUUUGACUCUGGAUAUUUUAUUUGUAUGCUAAUUUUUUUAAUUUAAAACUUUGUGGCAUCUUUGAGAAACGCUAUCCCAAGAGCCUUAUAAUAUAUUAAUUAUUUAAAAAUUUUCUAUUCCCCAGUGUUGAAUAUUAUCUUGAAAAUACCCUACAAAUUUUAGUUGUUACUUUUUUAAAAAACAAUUACGAGGCUUAAAUAAAAAAGAGUACCAGAAUGUAUAUUUCCAAAUGAGGAUUCUUGAGAGUAGUCUUAUUGGUAGGUUAUGCAUUUAUUUCAGUGGUGAGACCAUUGUGAUAGCCAGCUGCAAGCCCUGAGUUGAUACUGAUUAUAAAGUCUGUUUUUAACCACCCAGAUGACCAAUUGUCAUCUUAUGUAUGGGUAUGCAGAAAGUACAACUGGCAGAGACCUUAGAUUUUAUAAUCCAAUUACAUAAAUGAGAAAACCAAGAAGAAGGAAUUUAUCUAAGAUCAAAUACCAAGUUAGAGGCAAAGUUGGAACUGGGACCGAGAUUGCCAGCCUCCCAAUAUAGCACUUUUAUAUUCCUCUGUUUUGCUGCUACUCUUGAUUGCUGGCAGAAGUGUUGGUUUCUUGGUCUCUGUGAUGAAAAAGACUUUAUAGGCUUGGUUAUUCUUCAUCUUUCCCAGCAAUUUGAAUCAAUUUUGUUAGAUAUAUACAACCACUUAAAUAACAGACUAUCACUUACUUAUGAUAACAGAAUAUAGAAGAUGGGUCAUCUGAAAACUUGUGCAAGGGAGACUAACUAAAAAUACCAGCAGUUUUUGUUUCCCGAAGACUGUGUUAAAGUGAGCUUUAGAGUCGAGCCCUGUGUACUGUAUAGUCCUGUUUUUCUCUGACUGCAUUGUGCUAGUUCUCUUUUCAAAUGUGAAUUAAAUUCAGUUAUGAAAGAUUA